GGCUCUGUCGGCAGUUUCUCCAGGACCCAGCAGUGCCCUCUGUCCACUGCUCUGGGCCAUUCCCCAAUCCCCCCUCCCACUUGAGCCCCUAACUCAGAAUCUGGGACCCAGGGGCCCCUCCCUACCCCAGCUAACCUCUUCUGGACCAGGAGAGCCAACCCAGAUCCCACUACCUCCAUGAGUGCUACAGACAGGAUGGGGCCCAGAGCUGUGCCGGGUCUGCGGCUGGCACUGCUGUUGCUGCUGGUGCUAGGGACACCCAAGUCAGGGGUACAGGGGCAGGAAGGGCUGGACUUCCCUGAGUACGAUGGUGUGGACCGUGUGAUCAAUGUCAAUGCAAAGAACUACAAGAAUGUGUUCAAGAAGUAUGAGGUGCUGGCACUCCUCUACCAUGAACCCCCCGAGGAUGACAAGGCCUCACAAAGACAAUUUGAGAUGGAGGAGCUGAUCCUGGAGUUAGCAGCCCAAGUCCUAGAAGACAAGGGUGUUGGCUUCGGGCUGGUAGACUCUGAGAAGGAUGCAGCUGUGGCCAAGAAACUAGGCCUAACUGAAGUGGACAGCAUGUAUGUAUUCAAGGGAGAUGAAGUCAUUGAGUACGAUGGCGAGUUUUCUGCUGACACCAUCGUGGAGUUUCUGCUUGAUGUCCUAGAGGACCCUGUGGAAUUGAUUGAAGGUGAACGAGAGCUGCAGGCGUUUGAGAAUAUUGAGGAUGAGAUCAAACUCAUUGGCUACUUCAAGAGCAAAGACUCAGAGCAUUACAAAGCCUUCGAGGAUGCAGCUGAGGAGUUUCAUCCCUACAUCCCCUUCUUCGCCACCUUCGACAGCAAGGUGGCAAAGAAGCUGACCCUGAAGCUGAAUGAGAUUGAUUUCUACGAGGCCUUCAUGGAAGAGCCUGUGACCAUCCCAGACAAGCCCAAUAGCGAAGAGGAGAUUGUCAACUUCGUGGAGGAGCACAGGAGAUCAACCCUGAGGAAACUGAAGCCGGAGAGUAUGUAUGAGACCUGGGAGGAUGAUAUGGAUGGAAUCCACAUUGUGGCCUUCGCAGAGGAAGCUGAUCCUGAUGGUUUCGAGUUCUUAGAGACUCUCAAGGCUGUGGCCCAAGAUAACACUGAAAACCCAGAUCUUAGCAUCAUCUGGAUUGACCCUGAUGACUUCCCCCUGCUGGUCCCAUACUGGGAGAAGACGUUUGACAUCGACUUGUCAGCCCCACAAAUAGGAGUCGUCAAUGUUACUGAUGCGGAUAGCGUAUGGAUGGAAAUGGACGAUGAGGAGGACCUGCCUUCUGCUGAGGAGCUGGAGGACUGGCUGGAGGAUGUCCUGGAGGGCGAGAUCAACACAGAGGACGAUGACGAUGAUGAUGAUGACUAGUUGCUAUGGCAACCAUCUUUCAGCCCCACUGGUCUUUUCAUGCUCUCUCCUGCCUUCCCUUGUCCUUCCCUGAGUUCCUCCAGGGAGACUAGGUUAUUCUCUGCCAUAGAGCUAACUGGGGUCUAUAUGCUGGGUGCUGAGACACUGAUCCCCCUCAUUUGAUGAGCAAAUGAGCUACUUUUCCCUAGACACCAGGCCAGCUCUCUCUUAUCUGACUUCUGUUUCUUAUCCCAUAACUUACUUGUAUCUAUUAUGUGUCUCUUCCAUCACUCUCCAUACUCUUUCUUGUGAUUCUCCUCUAGCCAUAUAUAUGGGCCCCAUCUCUGUUCUGUUCCCUCCAUCUAUGCACAGCUUUCCCCCACUCUCUCUAAUCCUGUAUCUUUCUGACUGUCCUGUCCUUGGCCAGAAGGAAGGGAGAAUACUGUGUUUGGGACUGUAUCUCAGCAAUCACUUGUUAAUGUAUUUGGGUCAAAUGAGAGGCCUCAAUAAAGACAUCUGGGGCAGCAUGAA